UUUCUCACAGUCUGGAGUCUGGAAAGUCCAAGAUGAAGGUGCUGGCAGAUUCACUGUGUGGUGAGGCUGCUUUCUGGUGAUGGUACCCUCUCGCUGCAUUCUGGCAUGGUGGAAGGAAUGAAGGGUCUCUCUGGGGUCUCUUUUAUAUGGGCACCAAUCCCAUUCAUGAGGGCUUUAGCCUUAUGACUGAAUCACCUCCCGUAGGCCCCACCUCCCGAUACCAUCACCUUGGGGGUUAGGAUUUCAACAUAUACAUUUGAGAAUGGAGAGGAGGGGACGCAAACUUUCAGCACUGACUGUCAUAUCCUCUCCCAUUAAGAGAAACUGGAAUGGAGGUAGGAGAGGGCCCAGGCAUCUAAAACAGCACAUUUGGUUGCUGCGUCUUGGACUCACCAUUACUAGAAGGGCUGGGUGUUCUGAAUGAGAACAGAGACCUUGGCGCGCCAAGCAGGGGCGGGGACCCCCUCCUAUGGUGCCUGCUCUCCUCCCUACCCCCACCCGGCCCUGAGCAGUGCCCACGUGGCUCUCCAGGAGCAUUUCCCAGCUUUUUUUUUUUUUUUUUAACUUUUAUUAGCUCAGACUCCUGGCUGCUGCAGCCAUAUGGAGCUCUGCCGACGGCUGCUGCUCAAAGAGAUGUGGCAUUUUGUUGUUUCUAACUUUAUCUUAACCAGGAGAGACACAGGAGCACAGCUGAGAGUGGGGAGUGCCCUCGUAUGCACCAGUCUAGGAACUGGGGAUGCAACAGGCAACCCACCAGGAGAAAACCAUGGCAGCAGCUGUUUCCCUUCCUCCGGGAGGGAUGGCAAGGACCCCAGAAGCCACCACCAGUACAGGACCUGGGCAUGGAGUCGACCUCGCUAGACGACGUUCUGUAUCGCUACGCCAGCUUCCGGAACCUGGUGGACCCCAUCACACACGACCUCAUCAUCAGCCUGGCACGCUACAUCCACUGUCCCAAGCCGGAAGGCGAUGCACUGGGCGCCAUGGAGAAGCUGUGCCGGCAGCUGACAUACCACCUCAGCCCCCACUCCCAGUGGAGGCGGCACCGGGGGCUGGUGAAAAGGAAGCCACAGGCCUGCCUCAAGGCUGUCCUGGCCGGAAGCCCCCCAGACAACACAGUGGACCUGUCGGGAAUCCCACUGACCUCCCGAGACCUGGAGCGGGUGACCAGCUACCUACAGCGCUGUGGGGAGCAGGUAGACAGCGUGGAGCUGGGCUUCACAGGCCUCACGGACGACAUGGUCCUGCAGCUGCUGCCAGCACUCAGCACCCUGCCCCGCCUCACCACACUGGCACUCAAUGGCAACCGGUUGACCCGGGCCGUGCUGCGCGACCUCACUGACAUCCUUAAGGAUCCCAGCAAGUUCCCCAAUGUCACGUGGAUUGACCUGGGCAACAACGUGGACAUCUUCUCCUUGCCCCAGCCCUUCCUGCUCAGCCUGCGCAAGCGCUCCCCAAAGCAGGGCCACCUACCCACCAUCCUGGAGCUGGGUGAGGGCCCAGGCAGUGGGGAGGAGGUCCGGGAAGGGACAGUAGGCCAGGAGGACCCUGGAGGGGGCCCUGUGGCACCUGCCGAAGACCACCAUGAGGGCAAGGAGACUGUAGCUGCAGCUCAGACGUGACAUGGAAGUGAAGGGCCUCACCAGGGAGUCCUUGUUGGGUAGAAUGGGCAAGGCAGGCAGGGGAGGGCGCUUCUCCUAUCAGGUGGGUUAAGGAUAUUGCCAAAAAUUGGCCUGGGCCACCCACCUACAGAAAGGCAAACCAUAUCAUCUGGGGAAGGGGAUUUGUGUUAAAACUUCCCGUUGGUCCUCUGCAUCUGCCCCCUAUCCCAUUAUCUGCCAUUUGGUUCUUAAGUCAUCCCAGGCCCCAGAGAACCCUCUCAGCUCAGCUCAUGGCCUUCCCCAAAGACUUGUGGAAAUGGGCACAUGGCUGGAGGUACUGUAAGCCUGAGCCAUUGUGAACACCAAGAGCUUUCCCCCAGAAAAAGAAUACAGUAGGGCCCCUACAUGUACUGCAUUACAUUUUUCAUUUAGGGGAACAAGCUCCAACCAGAGGAAUGUGUCCCCACUCAAGGAAGGUGGGAAUCUUUAGCAAAAUUCCUGUAACUCCUGGUUGCCCGAGACCCCAGUUCCAUCUAUGCUAGGGGUGGACUGAACGUGGCCUACCUCCUUAUGGAGACCCAGCCCUAUUUCUGAGGCCCACCUUGAUUCUAGGCAUCUGCCCAUAGGACCAGCUAUCGCUAUAUCCUUUGACAGAGCAGCCUACGAUGCCAUGUGGUAGUGCUCAGGACAGACAUGGUGCCCAUGCAUACAGGCAUAAAGUCCUGUUCAGAAAUCCCCUAUCCACCUUCCCUACCCACUGCUGGCUGAAAAACUACCAGACUUCUAUGUGGGCUCUGAUGUCCUUAGCAUGCAGGGUAAGUGACAAACCUGGCUUCCUUCUUGUCACUUGCCAGUAUGACUUCACUGACCUAGACAGGCCGUAAGAACUCUUUCCCCAUAACUCUUAAGUAAUCCACCAACACAUUCCAGAAAACCGACUGCAGAAGGUGGGCUUUAAAACCUUAAAAACCUAGGACAAUGAAGGAGUCCAAUCCCUUGGCAGAUCCAACAAGAUGGCUGGGGAGAGGGAGAAACAAACUGGAGGCUCCCAAAGGAACCUAACUUAGCAAAGGUUCUCAUCUUAUACCCUCCCCUUACCCAAAUACUGUCCUACUGAAAGGGCCCUACCAGUUAAGGGAUCUCUUCUAAAUAACAGGCAACCCCUAGAUCCAAGUAGUUCAGUCCAGGAAGACUGGGAGCCAAUCACUCUUGAACCUUGUGGGCAAACAGUAUGGGGGAGGACCCUCUUGACAGGCCUUGGUAGGCAAGAUUCCAACACAGGAAGACAGCAAGAUGGGGCCUAGAGUAUGGGGCCCUACAUGCUGUUAAGGUUGUGGUUAGGAAUGGUGCAAUGCUGCAGGAGCUGGAACAAAGCUACACCAAGGAACAGAGCACAGAGCAGCAGGGGCCGAAAUUGAGGAGGCCUUAAAUGCUUUGAGCUUUUGCCUUCAGUCUAAAGCUGUAGAAUAGGGGGUUAAGAGCUUAGGCUGACCACAGGGAAGUUUACAAGCUAGAGCGAAUAUCUGGACUGCUAAUAUCUGACAACAGUAGGCGAAAUUUACUUUUUCUUCAAAUACACAUUUUCAAGAAUUGACACCCAAGACCAUCCUUUAUUGUAGUAUUAGUUCAUGGUAACUGCAUGAAAAAACAUUUCAGGAGGAAUUUACAAUUUCCAGCUUAAAGAACUUUGCCCACCAACAUAACCAAUUUAUGAAAGUCAAUUCAUUAAAAGGUAUAGAACCUCUUGUUGGGCAUGAUGGCAAGGGACAAAGCUACAACUUGGCCUGUGCCUUUGGAAGCUGAGGCAGGAGGACCAUCUGAGCCCAGGAGCCUGAGACCAGCCUGGGCAACAUAGAGAAUCCGUCUCAACAAAAAAAAAAUUUUAGCCAGGUGUGCUGUGAGCUGUAGUCCCAGCUACAAGGUGGGAGGAUUGCUUAGGCCUGGGUGAUUGAGGAUGCAAUGAGCUGUGAUUGUGCCACCACACUCCAGCCUGGGCAAUACAGCAAGACUGUCUCAAAAAAAAAAAAAAAAA